AUGCCCAAGAAUAAAGGUAAAGGAGGUAAAAAUAGACGCAGGGGUAAGAAUGAGAAUGAAUCUGAAAAAAGAGAACUGGUAUUCAAAGAGGAUGGUCAGGAGUAUGCUCAGGUAAUCAAAAUGUUGGGAAAUGGACGGCUAGAAGCAAUGUGUUUCGAUGGUGUAAAGAGGUUAUGUCACAUCAGAGGAAAAUUGAGAAAAAAGGUUUGGAUAAAUACCUCGGACAUUAUUUUGGUUGGUCUCCGAGACUACCAGGAUAACAAAGCUGAUGUAAUUUUAAAAUACAAUGCAGACGAAGCUAGAAGUCUGAAGGCAUACGGCGAGCUUCCAGAGCAUGCUAAAAUCAAUGAAACUGAUACAUUUGGUCCUGGAGAUGAUGAUGAAAUUCAGUUUGAUGACAUUGGAGAUGAUGAUGAAGAUAUUGAUGACAUCUAAAUUGAACUCAACAUUUUACAUUCCAUCUUUUCUGAAGAUUGUCCUACAAUUUGGAUUUUGAUCAUGACAAAGAAGAUUAAAAUUUCAUUAGCAUGAAUGCAAUUUGUUAAAGCAGACUGAUUUGUUUCUAAGAUAUUUUUGGUUUUUUUAAAACUGAUAAUAAUGCUGAAUUAUCUUAAGUGAGAUGUUAAGCCCACUUUGUUCUUUUAAUGUAAUGGAGCUUAUGGGUAGAAGACCAUGUCUACUAAUUACAAAAAAAAAAAAAAAACCAUGCAUUGCUGCUUUUCCUACCACUUCCAGUAAGAAAAUGGGUGUUUUGAAGAAAUCAUUUGCCUUGUCCUCACGGAAUCUGAUUAAGCCCUGGCCUCUUGAUUGUAUAGAGUCAUUGUGUAUAUUCCAGUUACCUAGAUAUUCCCUUGAGAUUUUGAUACAAUUUGAGGGAGGCAGAAGUCUGCAUUUGAAGAAAAAAAAUAAGUCUGUUUGUCAUAUUUAAGUAGCCUGUGGCUAUUUUUAUACUGAUUUUGAUAUCAUGUUCUUUUCAUAGUCGUAUUUUGCCACCGUAAACAUAAAAAAAAAAAAAAAAGAUUUCCAAAAUGCCGUUUUCAGAACCUGGGUUUUAAUAGCAGUAUUGAAUUUGUAAGCUUAGUAGUUGCAGAAAUUGAACACUAGGUGGCACUCAGUUAUCUUAACAGGGGAAGUACUGAUAUAAUUGUUGACUUUUCUUUUACUAUGUGUAAGAAAUACCCCAAACAUGAAAAGAUUGUUUUGAUCAUAUGCAUGUAUGUAGAAUAUUUUUGCAGAGCAGAAAGAUUAUGUUAGAAGUGUGAUUUUUAUUUUCAGAAGUCAUAUACAUGUAAGCUACAAUUUUGAGUGCUUUAUAAACACUUAAGAUAUAUAUAUAAAUUUUAAUUUCAUAGCAACUUGUAAAAAAUAAAAUACUUGUUGAAAAGCCUUUUUCAACAUAUCCCUAAGCUAAGGGAAGAGGAAGGAAUAACAACUCAGUGAAAAGAUGGUCUCCAAUUUCUGAAUGAAAAAGCUACAGCUGAGAAAUAAAAUAAAAUGUCAUGCUGCAGAAUAUGUUAUACCCUUA